AUUCUUUUUAUUUAAUUUUCUGGUCAGGAUAAUGGUAUCAUUUACCAGUUUCUUCUCUAUUUUAUAUAGAUGAUUGGUUUGCUUUUUCUCUUUUAUGUAAGCAAAUUUUAUGUUAAGGGUACAUGAAUAGGAGAGACUACUUCUCAUGGCCAAAUGGAGUUGAUUUUUGUAUCAUUCCUUAUAUAAUACUCAAGAACACUUUUAUUCAUGACUGUCAAAGUGCUGCUUCUGUAGGACUAUCAGAAUAAGAUUUAGUUGGACUAUUCCAGCCAUCCCUUGAGUGAUGACUGAUCAUUCCGUUUGUAUGUUAUUUGGGAUUCUUGCAUGGCCUGGAAUCUCCUAUUAUCUCCCUUUGGGUUAGUUCACAGUCCUUAACUCCACAAGAGUGGACACUUAUUUUAUUCUUCAGUAGAUCUUGGAUUAAAUAUUUAUUUUGCAAACUAAUGGCUAAAACAGAAGAGUCCUGUAGAUUUCAGUUAUCUGUGAGAUCCCUCCAUUGGCCCCUCAUAAAUGAAUGAUUGGGAAUUGCUUUAUUUCAUACCAUGUUCCUAGAUAGGGUUUCCUUGAGAAUCAAUCUUCCUACCAUAUUAAGGAUCUGUGGAGAAAUGCUUGCUGUUUGGACUGUGAAUUCUUACCCUGGUAUUUUACUGAAGAAACCUUGAGUAUUUGGUGGCUGGAAUGGGGGAAACAGUGGAGAGAACAGGCUCUGUUUUCCAGUCCCAGCCAGUAAUGAUGCUAAGAGAGGCAGAAUGUCUUGAACUGGACAAGGUCACUCAGUUUAAGAUAUUUUUUUCUAGGACUUUCCAUUGGGUCAUCAUGGAUAACUGCCCGGUUCAGAUUUGCUUAACAAGAUUAAAUUCCAUGGGCCAUUUUAAGAUCAAGUAUUUCUUACACUCACGUUAGAUUUCGGGUCUGACUUUGGCUUGGACACAUGUAGCAUGCUUAAAACUUUUCCCCCAAGUGGCUGCUUGCCAGCUUGUUUAGCUGAACCGACCUUGUCUGCUGACACAGCCUGAAGAGUGUCACACAUACGGAAUUUAUAUUAAGCAAUCUAGUAGUCCUUGUAAUGUCAUUUCACAUUCAGAACAUUUUUUUAAAUUAAAGGAAAAAUGAAAUGUCUCCUUAAGUGGAAGAGAACGACUUCAAAUUGGGACUUUGGGAGUUGAGUAGAAAACAUCAAACUGGCCAUUGCAGACAAAUCGUUUCCAGUUGGUGAAUAAGAAUAGGCUGUGGACCUCAGAGCUUAAACAUAAAAGGCAGCAGGAAAACUUGUGUUUCUUUCAGUACUGAAGUAAAAAGGAAACAUUUAUCUUGCUGCAUCCAUCCUUACAGUAAUGAAAGUUGACUAGAAAAACCAGACAAGAGCUAUUUAAUUUGUUUAUUUGCAAACCUUCAGAUGUGGCAGAAUAAUCUGGAAAGCCAGAGUUCAUUAUGUCUUCCUCAUUCUGGGACAGCAGGGGCAUUUUCAUUUAUAUAUUUUAUCCCACAAACAGCAAAAGACAAAUCAGUUAGCACUUCUUCCUCACUGUCCAAAAUUAUGAGGCAUUGGCAAUAGCACUAAUUGUUUUCUUUGUGUUUUGUUAGGACGGCUUUUGCAUCAUAUAAGGAUUGUGUCUAAGUUGGGUUUGCAAUGUACCCUGGCAAGGUUAACUUUCAGUAACAUUUUUUGCUUUAUGAAUCUUUACCUCCUUUAAUCGUUGGGUGGAAUUUUAUUGGAGUGGUGCCAAAAAAAAGUUUACGUAGUAGGAUUAAAAUAAACCAAAAAACAGAAACUCUUAGCAAUUCUUUCAUUAAUGAUGUUAAUGAAUCAGUCUGGGACACUUGAUAAUUGUUUCUUGUAAACAUUUAAGUGACUAAUUCCAAGAAAUGAUCUUUGCUAUGCAGUGGAGUAUUCCCAGUUUUGAUGGUAGAGCCCUUCCCUCAAUUAACAUUUUUUCAUCUUUAGACCAUAAAGUGGCAAUUGUCAGUGAGCUGGGCUGGCAGGAGCAGGGAGGGUUGAGAAGGAGUGUGUAAGUAGACCGUGGAAAGGGGAGAGAGUGGGUGAGGCCACACUCCCAGUGUGGGGGCCUUGCAGGCUUGUCCAGUGUGACAGCGGUCACCUGUGUGGUGUGUGUUUAUCUGGCUGGGAGAGGAAGGAGCAUUUUGUUUCCAUGAAACUGCAAUAAUUGUAUACCCUCAUUUAUAAUAUGGAUAAUUCAGAUAUUGAUGGAAUAUCUGAAUAUGGAUGGAAUGGAGUUCAACUUUAUGCUGGUUAUGGUGGAAAAAGGAUUUGCUAAACAAAGUAUCAUUGUAAACAAUGCUUUAGAGGACUAUUUAACUUUACAAAAGAGAACACACUGUCAAGCACUUACGGAACUGUCAUCCUCAAACCUUGUGUCAGUUAUGAUAGUCUCCAUAUGCCCAUUUAGGGAUUCAUUUAAGGUCUGGCAGACUUGCUCCUCAGGAAUACUUCACCAUCACUUGCUUUGUAUUACUAUAUGGAUUGAAAGUAAUGCAGCUGCCAUUAACAAAAUGUGUGUAUUCUCCAUCCAUCCAUCCACCCAUUCACCCAUCUACCUAUCCAGCCAUCGACAUAUCUACCCAUACAUCCACCCAGACACCCAUUCAUCCACCCAUCCAACUGUCCAUUCAUCCAUCCAUCCACAUACCCAUCCACCUGUCCAUCUACCCAUUCACCCAUCUACUCAUCCACUCAUCUGCCCAUCCACCCACCCAUCCGUCUACCUACCCACCCAUCUGUCAUCCACCCAUCCAUUCAUCCAUCCAUCCAUCCAUCCGCUCAUCUAUAUAUCUACCCAUCUAUCCACCCAUUCACCCAUCCACCCACCUAUCCACCUAUCCAUCUGUCUACCCAUCCACCCAUCCAUAUAUCUCCCCAUCCAUCCACCCAUUCACCCAUCCAUCCACCUGUCUACCCAUCCAUUCAUCCAUCCAUCUAUCCAUCCAUCUACCCAUCCACCCAUCCAUAUAUCUACCCAUCUGUCUACCCAUGCAGCUAGCACCUACCCAUCCACCUAUCCACCCAUCCAUUCAUCCAUCCAUAUACCCAUCUACCCAUUCAUCCACCCAUCCACCUAUCCAUGCACCCAUUCACCCAUCCCCCAUCCAUCCACCCAUUUAUCCAUUCAUCCAUCUAUUCAUUAA